AAGAAUUUUAUAGUUCUGGCUCUUAAUUUAGGUCUUUAUGUGUGGAUAUCUAUUACCAUAUACGUGGUUUUUGCAUUACCAUUUGUUGAGAAAACUGUCCAUUUCCCAUUAAAUGGUCUUGGCACCUUUGUUGAAAAUUAUUCGACCACAAGUUUGAGGGUUUAUUUCUGGGCUGUGUAUUCUAUUCCAUUGGUCCAUAAGUUUGUUUUUAUGCCAAUACCACUCUAUUUUAAUUACUGUAGUUUUAUAGUAACUUUUGAAAUCAAGAAGUGUGAGACUCCACUUUGUUCUUUUCAAGAUUGUUUUGGUAGUUUGGGAUUCCUUGAGAUGCCAUAUGAAUUUUAGGAUGGGUUUUUCUAUUUCUGCAAAAAAUAGGCUAUUAGUAUUUUGUUAGGAAUUGUAUUGAAUCUCUAGGUUGCUUUGGGUAAUGUUGACAUCUAAAUACUGUCUUCCAGUCCAUGAACAUGGAAUAUCUUUCCAUUUAUUUGUGUCUUUAUUUCAGCAGUGUUUUUUAGUUUUCAGUGUAAAAGUCUUUUGUCUCCUUGUCUAAGUUUAUUCCUAAGUAUUUUAUUCUUUUUGAUGUGAUUGUAGAUAGGAUUCUUGUCUUAAUUUCUCUUUUGGAUUGUUCAUUGUUAAUGUUUAAGAAUGCAACUCAUUUUUGUGUGUUAAUUUUGUAUCCUACAACUUUACUGAUUUAUUAGUUCUAAUAGUUUUUUUGUGUGUGGAAUCUUUUUUGUGGAGUUUUCUACAUAUAGGAUCGUGUCAUUUGCAAACAGUUAAUUUACUUCUUGCUUUCGAAUUUGGAUGCCUUUUAUUUUUUUCCUUGCCUAAUCUCAGCUAGGACUUCCGGUACUGUGUCGACUAGAGGUGGUAAAAGCAGGCAUCCUUGGCUUGUUCCUGAUCUUAGAGGAAACGUUUUGAGUCUUUCCCUGUUGAAUAUGAUACUAACAUGAGUUUUUUAUAUAAGACCUUGAUUAUGUUCAGGUAGUUUCCUUAUAUUCCUGGUUUGUUGAGUGUUUUAACAGGUGUAUUUUAAGAAAAAUCAUUUGUGGGUGCUGAAAAGAAAGAAUUUCUAGCCUGGUGAGUGAGAGAAUCCUGGAGUCAUUGACAGAAUAAUAUAUUAUCAUGAAGUUGAUGUUUUAGGCAUCAUCUUUGUACAUUUACAGACCUGUUUUGAUUGAUAAAAAUAAUACUAUAGUUAUUUAGUGGGGAAGACUGACAUUACUCAAAUAAUUAUGCAGAUGUAUGUCUGAAUAACUAUAGUACAACUGGCUCACAUUUGUAUUUCUAGUAUCUAGCACUGUGCCUGGCACAGGGGCAUUCAGUGAAGUUGCUAAUUGAAUCAAGAAGCAGAAGAGUAAGGUUUAACCCAGUAAAGUAAAAAACAUAUUAUUAUAUAAUUUUUUAAUGGAAAUAAUGUUUAUUUUUAUUUUACCAGUUUUUAAUUUUCUUGAGACAGAGUCUCACUUUGACAGCGGGCUGAGCGCAGUGGUGUAGUCAUGACUCACUGCUGCCUUGGCCUCCUGGGCUCCAGCAAGCCUCCUGCCUCAGCCUCCCGAGUAGCUGGGAAUACAGGCACGUGCCACCAUGCCUGGCUAAUUUUUGUUGUGAGAGACAGGGCCUUGCAGUGUUGCCUAGGCUUUAUUUAAAACCAUUUUCCCUGUUAACCCAGUCUUGGUACAAUGGUAAUAAAGCAAAAUCAAAGUUCACCACUCUAGAAGAAUUAGGCAAGUGACUUUUUCUAAAACAGGUAUAGUAUCAUUAUUAAAGUGAGGUAACAGUUUUUCUUUUGACUUUUUUUUUUUUUUAGACAGAGUUUUGCUCUGUCGCCCAGGCUGGAGCGCAAUGGCGUGAUCCUGGCUCACUGCAACUGCUGCCUCCCAGGUUCAAGUGAUUCUCUCCUGCCUCAGCCUCCCAAGUAGCUGGGACUGUAGGUACGCGCCACCACACCUGGCUGAUUUUUGUAUUUUUAGUAGAGACAGGGUUUCGCCCCAUUGGCCAGGCUGGUCUCAAACUCCUUACAUAAGGUGACCCACCCGCCUCAGCCUCCCAAAUUGCUGGGAUUAUAGGCGUGAGCUACCAUGUCUGGCCCAGUUUUCUUUUUGGGUGAAUGCUAGUGGAAGUUAGUUAUCAGAAUCCAAAGUUUCAGAAGGAGGCUUUUUGCUCUGUCGCCUAAGCUGCAGUGGUGCAAUCACGACUCACCAGAACCUCAACUACCUGGGCUCAAGCAGUCUUUCCACCUCAGCCUCCUGAGCACCUGGGACUAUGGGCAUGUGCCACUAUGCCUGGCUAACUUUUGUACUUUUUCUGGAGAUGGGGUUUCACUGUGCUGCCCAGGCUGGUCUCGAACUCCAAGACUCCAGCAGUCCUCCAACCUUGGCCUCCCAAAGUGCUGGGAUUAUAGGUGUGAGCCACCAUGCCCAGCUGAGGCAUAAUUUCAACGAAACUUUUCAAGUGUCUGCUGAUUCCAGAUUUAUAAUGAAAUUUGAACAUUCAGCACUUAUUUGCAGAACAAGUUCAAAAGUUAAGAACCACCACGCUGUGGUGGUUUUUUGUUUUUGUUUUUUUAAUUUUAAAAUUUUGGACAGUUUGUAAAUUUGACAUCACAAAUUGAAUCUUUCAGAUACCCUUACUAUUUCAAAUAAUAUAGUAACUUUAGAAACAUAAUAUACUUAGUAUUAUAAAUUGACAUUAAAUCCAUGUCAUUGUGUGACAUGUGAGCAUUAUGUUAAGAUUGAAAUAGAUGGGGACACUUGGAAUAGCUAGGAAACACUUUAAUCCAAUACACAGAACAUUCUUUAAGUUACAGGAUUCAAAAUAGUUCCCUUUUAGAGCAUCGUUGGGGUUUUUAGAUAUAGUUGUGAUAGAACACCAGACUGGGAAUCAAACCUCCAUUUAGAUUCUGACUGAUGUUUAUAGUUUUAUGAUCUUAAAGCAAGUCACUUAACCUAUCUGAAGAUUAAUUUUCUCAUCUGUUAAAAUAGGUAUGGAAAUCUUGAAGCUUUUCUACCUUGUAUGUAUUUUUUUACUCCAUUGUUCCCCUCUCUAUUGCCACUCCCUUAUUAGUCUGGACUACGUAUUAAACAGCCUGCCAGCUAAGUCUCUGCAACUUGUUCUCCCACUGUACCUCUCCAUCUCUGGCUAUUCUCUAUAUUACUAUGACAAUUAUGUUCUUAAAAAACAGGCCAGACACGAUGGCUCACACCUGUAAUCCCAGCACUUUGGGAGGCUGAGGUGGGCGGAUCACCUGAGGUCGGCAGAUCACCUGAGGUCAGGAGUUCAAGACCAGUCUGGCCAACAUGGCGAAACCCCAUCUCUACUAAAGAUACAAAAAUCUGGUGUGGUGGCAGGUGCCUAUAAUCCCAGCUACUUGGGAGGCUGAGGCGGGAGAAUCGCUUGUCCCCAAGAGGCGGAGGUUGCAGUGAGCCAAGAUUGCGCCACUGCACUUCAGCCUGGGUGAUAGAGCUAGACUCUGUCUCAAAAAAAAAAAAAAAAAAAAAAAAAUUGGAGCAUGCUGCUUCUCUACUUAAAAUACCUUUGUUAACUUCCCUUGUCGAUAAAGUCCAGACUCACAAGAGUUUAUAGAAUGUGUUCAACCUUAGGUCUCCUGUCACUCCAGCCAUGCUGUUUCUUGUUCCCUGUGCCUCUGUCUUGUGUGUGUUUAUCCCAUUGUUUGGAGUUCUUAUUCUUUGCCUAUUCUGUUAGCUGCCCAUCUAAUGUCUACUUUUCUCUUCUUUCCUAACAGAAAUCUGCUUUUGUUCAUGCAUGCAGCAGACUUGGAGAAGCUGAUUUGUCACCACCUCCAGUAGUAGAGUUCCAUUAGUUCAAACCAGUCAAAUCAUGGCAUUUCCCUGUAAACUCUUAUUUGUACCGAUCAGAUUUGAAGGGAAGUAGACAUUCUGUUUCUGGGGGAGAAGAUUCUUUCCUCUCUUGUAUGUGAACAAGGGAACACAAGGCCCCUAUUGCUACCGACAGCUGUCUUGGGAUCACAAGGGAUGAAGCACUUCCUGAAGAUGGCAGAUCAGAGAGGUAGAGGGUAUCUGGAUCCUUGGUAACAUCAUUUAACCACAUAUUUUAUUGGGCCUGGAGCCAUCCCCACCACAGGACUUCUCAUGACAGAUAAUUUUCUUAAUGUUUCAGACAGUUCUUUGGAGUUAUUUGCCAUCAAAAAUCUCUUUUUUUUUUUUUUGAGACAGGGUCUCGCUCUGUCACCCAGGCUGGAGUGCAGUGAUACAAUCACAGCUCACUCCAACCUUGACCUCUUGGGUUCAGCAGUCCUCCUGCUUCAGGCUUCUGAGAAGUAGCCACCACACCUGGCUACUUUAAAAAAAUUAUUUGUAGAGGCAGGGUCUCCCUGUAUUGCCCAGGCGUCUUGAACUCCUGGUCUCAAGUGAUCCUCCCACCUCAGUCUCCCAAAGUGUUGGGAUUACAGGUGUGAACCACUGCACCUGGCCCAAAAUCUCUUGAUUGAUACAGUCCUCUUUAUUUUUCAAGAUCAAGUUAUGAUACCUUUACCAACAGUCAUACAUUCUUUUGGAACUUUGCACAAUAGUCAUAUGUUCUUUUAGAACUUUACACUUCUAUUCUUUAUUGCCCUGUAUUAUAAUUGCUUGUAUGCCUGACUCCUCUACAUGACUGUAUGGUUUGAACCAAAGUGUACGGGAUGUCGCACAGUGUCUAAUAGUGUCACACAACAAGUAAUAGGUAUUCAGUAAGUGAGUUAAGAUGAAAUAGUAACAUGAAAGAGUGCUUUGAAAGCAGUUUUUUAAAGAGUUUCUGUUCUGCUAAUUGUAAGCCAUUUUUUAAAUAAACAUGACGUGUGGUGUUGUCUUUAAAGUAAAAAUGGAAAAACCAGUGAGAUCAGACAUUGUUUUUUGCUUGCCCCUCAUUAUUACCUAGACAUUUUCAUUUAGAUAAAAACUAUGUCAGUCUCCUGGCUGUAGUCCUUUACGGAAGGAGCAAUAUUACAUUUAGCUCUGUUUCAUCUGGGAUUCAAUUGUGAAUUAUUCUUUAGAGAAAAAUUCUAUAAUAUGCUUCAUGAGACCUAUUCUUGUCUUCAGACUUGCCUAAAAUAUUUUUUGCUUGCUUAAGACCAGACAUGAGAAUUUUCUUGUAAGCAGAAAGCUUUGUGACAGGACUGGAUGAGUUUGUAGUGAAUGUUAGUGAUAGCUAUGACAGAAGUCUCAUAGCCUCAAUUGCAGAGUCAUAGUUCUGUCACAUGCUUCAACAAUAAUGUCUGAUAAGGGAGGAAGGAUGGGGAAGAAGAGUUACAAUUUACUAACUGUAUAUAUUUCAUCAUUUAUUGGCUUUGGUCAAAUAAAUUAAACAUUAACAUAGUAAUUUGUAGGGUUAAAAAAAUUUUUUUUUUCUAUUCGCGUUCUUGCUAUGUUCCCCAGGCUGGUUCCAAACUCCUGGGCUCAAGCGAUCCUCAAGCCUUCUGAGUAAUUGAGAUUGCCACACCCAGCUUUGCAGUGUUUGUUUUUUUUAAGAGACAGGAUACUCAUUCUGUGCCCAGGCUGGAGUGCAGUGGCCCUAUCAUAGCUCACCGCAGCCUCAAACUCAUAGGCUCAAGAGAUUGUCCUGCCUCAGCCACCUGAGUAGCUAGGGCAGCAGGCACACGCCAUCAUGCUCAGCUAAUUUGUAAACAUUUUUUUUUGUAGAGAUGGGGUCCUGCUGUGUUGUUGCCCAGGCUGGUCUUGAACUCCUGGCCUCAAGCAAUUCAUCCCAUCUUGGCUUCCCAAAGCACUGGAAUUAUAGGCAUGAGCCACAUCACCCAGCCUUGUAGUUAUUUUUAAAAUGAAGACAAGAGGAAUAGAGUAUACCUUUAAAAAUAUAUGAUACUGUGUAUUGGAUGAUUCUGAAAGGAUGUAUUUGCCUAUGAAGAAAAACCUUCUUGUUUUGAUGUCUGGUUGUUAGCUUUUUACUUUACUAAAGCCCAGUUAACUUUUCUGUGCUUUAGUUCCACAUCUGUAAAAUUACUCAUUUUAUAUUUCUCUAUCCACUUUGAAAAUUAAGUAAAUGCUCUUUGAAUUUCAACUUUUAAUUAUUUAAGCCAAGAUCUCUCUUCUGUAUUUUUUAUGUGUUCUUUAUUGUGGGCUUACUAAUUCUUGAAUUUAAAAAAAUCAUUUAAAUCAAGCAAUAGUAAUAGUAUAUGUUUAAGCAUAUAGUGUAUGUUUUUAAAUAAAUAAGCAGGCUGGGUUUUAGUGGCUCACCCCUAUAAUCCCAACACUUUAGGAGGCCAAGGCAAAAGGAUCACUUGAGUCCUGGAAUUGAAGACCAGUCUGGGCAACAUAGCGAGAUCACACCUCUACAAAAAAAAAAGUUUAAAAAUUAGCCAGGUAUGGUGGUAUGUACCUGUAGUUCUUAGCUAUUCGAGAGGCUGAGGUGGAAGGAUCGCUUGAGCCCAGAAAUUUGAGGUUAUGGUGAGUAGCGAUCACCCCACUGCACUCCAAGCCUGGUUGACAGAAUGAGACCCUGUCUCUAAAAUAAAAAUAAGCAAUAGCAUAUUUUUUUAAAAAACAACAAACAACUCUUUUAAGUCCAAAUUCCUUUUUGGAUCCUAUGGCUCAUAUCUUGCCACUGCCUGCUGCACUCUAUAUAGAAAUACUUUUAUUUCCUUCAGGAAUCCAGUUUUGUUCUCUCCGUGGGCCUUCUCAUAGUUAGUUCCCACUGCUGUUUGGAGCAUUAUUUUGGCAUUCUUCUCGCUCCUUCUAUUAUUUUCACCAAGAAAAGAGGAAAGCUCACACUUUCUAUUGUCAGUCUUGGAUAUCAUCCCAAAUGUCACUUUCUCAAGAAUCGUUUAAGAUAAACAGUUGUAUUAUCAGCCACAAAGAAGAUUAAAAAAAAAAAUUGCCCAAGAUCAUACAGUUUAGAAAUGGCAGAGUCAGAUCCAAACUUGGGCAGUUUUGCUCCAGAAGUCUUUAUCGCCACUGAUUUAUGCUUCCCCUACAUUGUAAUUGCCUGUUCAACAGUUUGCCCCACUAUGAGCACCUUUGGGGUAUUGUUUGCUUGUUUGUUUGUGACGGAGUCUUGCUCUGUAGCCCAGGCUGGAGUGCCAUGGCGCGAUCUCAGCUCACUGCAACCUCCACCUCCCGGGUUCAAGCGAUUCUCCUGCCUCAGCCUCCCGAGCAGCUGGGAUUACAGGCACGCACCACCACGUCCAGCUAAUUUUUGUAUUUUUAGUAGAGACGGGGUUUCACCAUGUUGGCCAGGCUGGUCUUGAACUCCUGACCUCAAGCGAUCCACCCGCCUAGGCCUCUGAAAGUGCUGGGAUUAUAGGUGUGAGCCACUGCCCCCCUUAAAAGAAGCACCUUUGGAGGAAAAAUUAUGCCUGUCUUGUUCAUUGUUAUAUCCCCAUGUGCUUAGCACAUACUAGGUGCUCAGAAAAUAUUUAAAUGAAUGAAAAUUCUUAUUUGAGGGAGAGAGUGUUUUGAUUAAAUUCUUCUCAGUACCUUUCAUGUAGUGUGUCAGUAAAUGCAGUAAUGUUUUCAUGCCUACUUAUUAUACAAAGUGAAAUUUUUAUGAUCAAGUUAAUCAUGGUUACAAGCUCAUUUUUUAUAACCUCUCUUAAUUCCUUUUUGCCCUAUACUGCGUAACGGUAUCACUUUGCAACUGUAAAAACUAGUGCUUUGUAGGCCUCUUUCUCAUAUUAUCCCUCUGUGAACUGUUAAAAUAUAGAUCAUUUUUAAUUAGUUUCUAAAGGGUAUGUAGGAAAUUGUAUAAAAUAAAAUUAUACUAGUAGAUGGACUCUGAUCAUUUAUACUGUUUAACCUUUUAACAAAUUACAGAGGUGUAAUUUCUCUGUGUGUAGAGGUUUUUUAAAGUAUCCCAUAUUUUAAACCUUGACUGUUACCUCAAAAAAAAAAGUGGUUUAUCUGUGUCCAGUAGUCACAUGGUGGAUAAUGAUGUAAGGCAUGCACAUUGUGUUCAUGUGUUUGUUGGAGAAGUUGGAAUGUCAUUAUACUUCAGUAGACUUUUCAAAUGAAAAAUCUGAAAGCUACUUCUAGCUGUAAUUCUGCUGUAAUUCUCAAUCAGGUCAGUAGACAGAGAACCAAAAAAGUCUUCCUCCUCUCUGAAUGUUCUUGCCAAAGCCUGACUUCUUUGAUUAAUCUUUCUUUUCUGUAUUCCUUACACUCUAUUACAGGGCUUCUCAACCUUGGCACUCUUGACAUUUGGGGCCAGGUAAUUCUUUGUUGUGGAGGACUGUCCUGUGCCUUGUGAAAUGUUUAGCAGCAUCCUUGGCUUCUACCUGUUAGAGGCAAAUAGUAUCCUUCCCCUUUCCCCUGUCCAGUUGUGGCAAUUUGAAAUGUCUCCAGACAUUGUCAAGUGUGGGGGUUAGGGAGGGUGGAAGGGGAGAACAAUCACCCCAGUUGAAAAUUGCAGCUUUCCUACAUCAUUCUGUCCACUUACUCAUUUGUUUUAAUAUCUUCCCCUCCCUCUCACACUUACCUUUUCAGACUUCCUGCCUCUCUGCUACUGCCUCAUUUCUCUGAACCUUUUUGCAGCCAUACUUCUAAAAAAGAAUUGUAAAACAUCUGUUCUCUCCAAGUUUUCACUUGCAGUUCAGUUUCCUCUUUUGAAUUCUAUUGAGACCACAUUUUUCUAGUUUUCCUCUAUCUCUCUGGCCGUUCCAUUUUUAUUUUCUUUAUCAGUUCUACCUAGUUGGACAAUGGCAUCAUCUUUGCCCCUUUCUUUCUUGUUCUCUGUUAUUCAACUCUCAAGUCUUCCUUUCUUGCCUCAUUUCCUAGUGCUUAAUGUUGUCUCUCAUAUGUGUUGUCCUAUUCAUUUUUAUUUUUUUUGGUAAGAACACAAUAUGAGAUCUACCCUUUCAACAAAUUUUUAAGUAUACAAUACAUUAUUGUUGACUAUAGGUACAGUGUUGUACAGUAGAUCUCUAGAGCUUACUCAUUUUGCUUAACUGAAACUGUAUGCCCGUUGAUUAAUAAGUCUGCAUUUCCCCCCAGCCCCUGACAACUCCCCUUUCACUCUUCGAUUCUAUGAAUUUGAUUAUUUUAGAUACUCACUUAUCAUUCUGGGUAAUGACCAGGCCUAGAUAAAGACCUCAUAUAAGUGGAAUUAUGUAGUAUUUGUCUUUCUGUGACUGGCUUAUUUUACUUAGCAUAAUGUCUUCAAGGUUCAUCCAUGUUGUCACCAUAUUUCCUUCUUCUCUGAGGCCAAAUAGUAUUCCAUUUAUGUAUUUACUACAUUUUCUUUAUUCAUUCAUCUGUCAAUGGAUAUUUAGGUUGUUUCCACAUCUUGGCUGUUGUGAUAUCUAUUAAUUGUUAAGCUGGUCUCUGUAUUGAAAUCUCCUUGCCUAUAUUUCUCCAUAGUUUAACAUCCUGCAAGGACCAGAGCAGAUUUUGUCUGUUGUUUUUUGGUUUUGGUUGUUGUUAUUGUUAGAGACAGUGUCUCAUUCUGUUGUCCAGGCUGUAGUGCAGUGGUGCAGUCAUGGCUCACUGCUCACUGUAACCUCAAAUGCCUGGACUCAAGUGAUCCCUCAUCUCAGCCUCCGGAGUAGCUGAGACUGCAGGCACACACUAUCACACUUGGCGAAUUUUUCUGUUUUUUUGUAACAGCCUGUUGCCCAGGCUGAUCUCAAACUCCUGGGCUGAAGCAAUCUGCCCACCUCGGCCUCCUGAAGUGCUGGGUUUACAGGCGUGAGCCCCCGCAUCUAGCUUGCACCUCAUUUAUUAAGGGUUCGUUAUGAGCCAGGCACUCUUUAAGGUCUUUGGACUAUAUAGUUACUGAAAUAAGACACAGUCCCAGUACUCCAAGAACUUAGUCUGUUUGAGGACAUGGAAAUUUUAAUUCAUUGCUCUUACAGAGUGAGUAUGGAAAUUGAAGUGUAUCCCAAACUUUCUGGUAGCAUAUAGGAAAGGGAUGAUUUCUCAGUUUGAUGUAAACCUCAUUCAAGUGCCACUUCUUACAUGCAGGCUAUCCUGGUCACUACCCAGUCUGAUUUGUGUUUUUAUACUCUCCUUUACUCAGUUCUCUUUCUUUUCCAGCCCCCAAAUCAUCAGCAUUUCCUAUGACUCAACACUUAGCUUUUCAUUCAUUCUUCUAGAUCCUUUUCUUUAGGAAAUGGAUUUAAUUUCAAGGGUUCAGCUGAAACUUUCAAAUUUGUAGUAGCUCCAACAAAACAUUUUAUUGUGAAGUAAUACACAUACAAAGUACAUUAAAUAAAUCUAACUUAAAAAAACAUUAUUUUAAAGCUGACAUCACUCUGGCCAUGAAAUAGAGCACUGUAAGUAUUCCAAAAGCCCCCCUCAUGCCUCUUCCCAAUCAUAACCACUUUCUUCCUCCUUUUAAAGGUUACUGCUAUUCUGAUCUUUAUGGUAAUUUCCUUGCAGAUUUUUAAAAAUAGCUUUAUUCUUGAUUACCAGCUGAAUAUUUAUCCCAAAACAAUAUAAUGUCAUUUUGGGAGGACAGUAGAGAAAGACAUUUUAUCAUAUCCCGUUUUGUGCCUGUAUUUUGAAUCCGCAAGAUCACCCCCAGGUUUGGUGAGGAGGAAGCACAGAACUCAACAUAUAGUAUGACUCAGCUAAGAGUUACUACAGCAAAAAAAAUACAAAGCGAAAAUGCCCAUGGGGCAACGUCCAGAGGAAACCAGGCACAAGCUUCAAGAGUCUUAUCCCAGUGAAGCCGCGUAGGAUGCAUUGACUUGUUACAAUCCUUGUGAAAUGUUGUCUUCCAGGGAAGCUUAUAAGAGACUCACUGCCCAGGGUGUUUAUUGGGGUAUAAUCACAUAGGCACCCUCUGUCUAGCUUGUACCAAAUUCCAAGCUCCCAGAAGGAAAGCAGAUAUUCAGCAUAAACCAUAUUGUUUGCACAAACAGUUUAGGCAUAGUAAAUCACCCUUAUUAAAUAGUCAGGGAAUUAUGGGAACACUCCCAAAAUCCAAUUUCCCAGAGACCUGCCAAGGGCCAUCUUUGCAUGCAGGCCUUUCUAAAGAUAGCAGUCUUAGGCCUGCUAUGUUGUCUUUUUGGCAUAGUACCUUUUGCUGUUUCUGAAUUCAAAAUUUAAAUAAGUAAAAAAUCAAUUAUCACUUUAUGUUAUGUUCUUUUUUUCUCCACCGUUGUUUUCUUUCCUAAUGUAUCAAGAUUAGCUGGGUGUGGUAGUGUGUGCCUCUGUAGUCUCAGCUACUUGGGAGGCUGAGUGCUGUAGUGCACAAUAAUUGCACUUAGGAUUAACCACUGCACUCCAGCCUGGGCGACAUACCAAACCCUGUUUCUCUUAAAAAAAAAAAAAAGUAUCAACAUUAGCUCAGUGCAAAGGUUGACUACUAUGAUAUGAUUGAAAGUAUAUUCCGGCCGGGCGCAGUGGCUCACGCCUAUAAUCCCAGCACUUUGGGAGGCUGAGGCAGGCAGAUCACUUAAGGUCAGGAGUUCGAGACCAGCCUGGCCAACAUAGUGAAGCCCCAUCUCUACUAAAAAUAAAAAAUUAGUUGGGUGUGGUGGCACAUGGCUGUAAUCUUAGCCGCUCGGGAGGCUGAGGCAGGGUAAUCGCUUGAACCCAAGAGGCAAAGGUUGCAAUGAGCUGAGAUCGUACCACUGCACUCUUUCUUAUGAAGGUUUCUGUGAUUAAGUUUGGAAAGGAUGAAUUAAACAAAGUUAAACAGAUUUCUUAACUACAGGACUCUUAGCCUUUUCACAGGAAUGUGCAUGACUUGGUGACUGCCUACAUGUCCUGCCUCAUCUCACGUUUUUUUUCCCUGACCCACUUUGCUUACUCUGCCCAGAUUUAAUCUAGUACUAAGGAUCAAAUUACAAUUGUCUAUGUUACAUGGGCAUUUUCUCAGUUUGCCACAGCAAUAUUAUGAUCACUUUACCAUCUUGAAUAUGAACUGUCCCUCCAUCUCUGCUCAAUUACUGUGUCAGAGCAAGCAAACGUUUUUACUAUUUCAUUCAUAGAUUCAGCAAAAUUUGUUAAGCACCUACUAUAUUUGCCAGACACAGUUCUAGGCACUGGAGAUACAACAGUGAAUAAAAGAAAAACCCUGACCUUAUAUAGUUUACCUUAUAGUGGGGAGUGGAAAAAGGGAACAAUAAUUAAAAAUACAUGUUAUGCCCAGUAUGGUGGCUCACACCUGUAAUCCUUAAACUCUGAGAGGCCAAAGUGGGAGGAUCACUUGAGGCCAAGAGUUCAAGACCAACCUUUAUAACACACCAAGACCUCAACAGAAAAAAUAAAAAUAAAUUAGCUGGGCACAGUGGUGCAUACUGUAGUCCCAGUUAUUCGGGAGGAUCACUUGAGCCCAGGAGUUUGAAGCUACAGUGAGCUAUGAUUGUGCCACCACACUUCAGCCUGAGUGACAGAGUGAGACUGUCUCUAUUUUUUAAAAAAAAUUAAAAAAAAAAAGACUGGGCAUGGUGGCUUGCACCUGUAAUCCUAGCACUUUGGGGAGGCCAAGGUGGGUAGAUCACCUGAAGUCAUGAGUUCGAGACCAGCCUGGCCAACAUGGUGAAACCCUAUCUCUACUAAAAAUACAAAAAAAUUAGCUGGGCAUGGUGGCAGAUGCCUGUAAUCCCAGCUACUCGGGAGGCUGAGGCAGGAGAAUUGCUUGAACCCGGGAGGCAGAGGUUGCAGUGAGCCGAGAUCACACCAUUGUACUCCAUCCUGGGCAACAAGAGCAAAACUCCAUCUCAAAAAAAAAAAAAAAAAGAUACAUUUUGCUCCUAGGCAUAUACUUAAGAGAAGUGGAAGUACAUGUCUACACAACUUGUACAAAUGUUUGUAACAGCAUUAUUCAUAAUAACCAAAAAGUGGAAACAACCCAAAUGUCCAUCAAUGGAUGGAUGGAUGAAUGAAUAAAUCAAAUACAAUGUGGUAUAUCCAUACAAUGAAAUAUUAUACAGCAAAUAAAGAGGAAUAAAGUAGUACUGAUAAAUGCUACAAUGUGGAUGGACCUUGAAAACAUCAUGCUAAAGUGAAAGAAGCCAGUCACAAAAGCCCACAUUAUUAUAUGAUCCCAUUUAUAUAAAAUGUCCAAAAUAAUAGAGGUAGAAAUUAGAUUAGUAGUUGCCUAGGAUUGGGGAAUUGAGGUGAGUGACUGCUAAUGGAACUUCUUUUAGGGGGUGAUGAAAAUGUUCUACAUGUCAGAACCACUGAUGGCUGCACAGAUGUAUCUACAAGUAAUAUAGUGUCAGUUAAGCACAACGUUCUCAAGAAAUUCAGUAAAAAGUCAAGCCUAACAUUGUACACCUCAAUGGCUAACAAAAGCAUCCUCCAGUUAUUUGGAAAAUUUAUCCAUCUCGCUUCCUAGCAACAGCAGGUAAUUGAGUUAGCUUAAUACUUAGGACUUAAUAAAAUGUUAAAUGUUAGUAUACCAAAUGACUUGAAACAAUAAUAACUGUGUUAUAAACUCUUAAUUUAAUGUUAACUUCCUCCUUAAUAGAAGAAUAUUUACCCACAUACUCUAAUUUGGAGAUUACAACACAAAUUGAAAGCACUUUCUCAAAUAUUGUCCUAACUGCUUAAAUAUUUAUAUAUAAAUUAGUUUUCUGAUGUAAAAAUGUUUGCAGUAAGAAGGAGGAAACCCAGAAGUUACAAAGGAAAAGACAGAGUUGUCUAUAUGAAAAAUUUAAACAUUUGUGACAAAAGCUAUCAUAGUUUUAAAAGGCCCGUAUGAAUAUUUUCCGUUUAUUAUUUUAACAUUAAUAUAGAAAAUGUUGCAAAUUUGUAAAAAGAACAGCCAAAUAGAAAAAUGGGCAAAGAAUAUAAAGCAACAUGGGGACUAAUGAAUAUCAGUUUAUUAAUUUUUAAGAGAUUAAAAUAGCAAUGGCAUAAUUUUUCCUCCAUCAGAUUGCAAAGAUGAAUAAUGUCCAGCAUUUUGGACAUUCUCAUGCAGAGCUGAUAGGAGUGUAAAUUGCAACUCUUCUGACAAUAUGUCUUCAAAUUAGAAACAUGUAUAUCCUUUAACCCAAGAAUCUUCUUGAAAUUUAUUCUAAUGACAUAAUUUAGACUGGGCAGAGUGGGCAAAGAUAUGUGUAAAAGACUUGCAGUGCUAUUUAUAAUAUUGAAAAAUUGGAUGUGACCCUCAAUAUGGAUUUGGUUAAGUAAAUUAUUACAUAUCUAUACAACACAGUUCUAUGUAGGAAUUUUUUUAAGGUAAAGUAAAAUUUUGUGUGUGGCCAUAUUUUUGCAACCUUGCUAUAUUAUGAAAUGAAAAUAGUUUUGUAUAAAACUGUCACCUGGCCAAAUUUUAAAUUUUGAUAUACAUAUGAGUGCAUAAUAGUUUUUAAUUUUAGGAUUUAGUGUAAAUUUAGUUUUCAUAAAUAAGAUAGUCAUAUCCACAUUUAAUAUUUUUUUCUAAUAAUUCAGUAUCUCUUUUAAUGAUUUCUUCACUGGUUUGGGUUUUCCUACCCUGUUUAAGAAUGAUAAUCUACAAGACUUCCCUACUGACUACUCUGGGUUUGUUACUCUUUGGAGAUUAUGUUUUUUAAAUCAUUUAAACAGCUAAGAGUUAACAGAUUUCAGACCUUGCUUACUAUGCAUUUAUAGCAGAUAUUUUAUUUAAGAAGUAUUUCAUAACUAGAAAUACUACAAGAACACUAAGAAUAUAGUUUCAGCCAGGUGAGGUGGCUCAUGCUUUGUAAUCCCAGUGCUUUGCAAAGCUGAGGCAGGAAGGUCACUUGAGGCUAGGAGUUCAAGACCAGCCUGGGCAACAUAGUGAGACCCGUCUGUACCAAAAAAAAAAAAAAUUUUGUUGUUCAUUAGCUGGGCACGCUGGCACACACCUAUAGUCCUAGCUACUUGGGAGGCUGGGGCAGGAGGAUUGCUUGAGCCCAGGAGUUGGAGGCUGCAAUGAGCUAUGAGUGAACUACUAUACUCUAGCCUAGACAACAGAGCAGGACCCUUUCUCAAAUUAAAAUAAAUGUGUGUGUAUAUAUGUGUGAUUGUGUGUGUGUGUGUGUGUGUGUGUGUGUGUGUGUGUAGUUUCAUUUUAGGAUAAGUCAAAAAUUCAGAUACUUUCCUCUUCACUAGACUCAGAAUUCUAAGAACCAUACUCAACUCAUUUCUCUGUAUUUCCAUCAUUUUCUAGUUUGAAAAAUUAUUCGAUUGUUGCAUAUAUUAGUGGAAUGUGAUGUACUUUUAUAUUCUUUUAAAAAUGCAUUUUUAAUGGGGAAAAAAGUAUCAGCAGGGGACUGACAGCUGUUAUGAAUUAUAAUAGGUUAUAUUAGAAAAAAACCACAUGGCUUAAUAAGAUUCUCCUAACAAAACCCUAACAACUAACUAAUCUUCAUUUGCAGUAAUGCAAUGGAAUUUUAUAGAAAAUGUCAAUUUAAAGAUUUUCAUUUAACAUGAAUAGAAAUGUUUUCUGACUUGACUAUUUUUGGUGGUGGGUGGAUAAGGGAAAAGACUAUUUUUAACUACAGGUCCACAUUCUCUUACUUAUAAUUUGAAAUCCCAAAAGUUCUGAAAACUAUUUUAGGGGUUAUGGGAGGACUUAAUUUGAUGGCAAACACUGACAUGACCUAGAUUUGUCUGCCAGCAAAACCGAACCUAAACUAACAUAGGUUAGUCUAAAUAGUAUAUUUUACUGCAGAAUAUUAAUUUGUUUGAUGUUACAAACAAAUUAUUACAAACAAAUUAGGGUGCUGUGCCAGAUCUCCCUGGGGAUAGUUAUAUAGUAUACAGUAAAUGUUUGGUAUACCAUAUGUCAUGCCAAACUUCUGUCACUCCAGUGGGCAUGGCAUUAGGUUCAAGAGGCCGAAGAAGAGACCCAGAGCCGGCAAAAGAGAUGUGGGGUUUUAUUGGGGGCUUACAUACAAAGGAGAGGGUACAGUGGCAGUGGGCUGGACGGGAGAACUGCCUUAUAUACAGUCCAGUGGCAGUGGGCUGGGCAGAAGAACCACAACUGCCUGCCAUAGGCAUGCAGUUUAUAUAGCAUUUCCACUUAGCACUUCCACCUAGCAACCUCCACCUGGCACUCUUUAUUCUACCCAAAACUUGGAGCCUCAGUCUCCUGUAGGGCUUGUGUUCCAAGAGACAGGUUGGGGGCUCAGAUGUCCUUAUAGACAAGGAGGGAAUCUCUGGGUUGGCCACUCCUGAAUUCCCUAGCUCAGAACACACAUUCAGGUGCAUCUGCCAUACAAAGUCAUUCUAAGGAUAUGCUUAAAUUAUUGCUGUCAGGUAUGUUUACUAUAACCAUAUUAUUUCUCUUUGAAAGCAAAAGAAAAAAGUGAAUUUUUGAAUGUAUGUGGCUCCAAAGAUUUCUAUUUGAAAAAGAAUUGUAGACCUGUAUUCUUAACACUCUUUAACUGGUACUUUAAGCUGAUGAUGAGCAUUAAAUAUAUAUUUUAUUGGUAGAACUAAGACUGAGAGUGUAGUAUGUAACCACUCUAUAGGUAAAGUUUAAUUAUCAAGAAUGUGGGGAGAAUAUAUGAAAUGUAAAAUAAGCUCACUGGUUAUAGGUAUUCACUGUAAAUAAAAAUAUAUCACUUAAAAUACUGGGGUAGAGACAGGAGAAGGAAGUUACUAACUUAAUUUCAGCAUUGCUCAUAGUAGGGAACCAACGGAUAAUAGCCAAAAAAACAGGGAAUGUAAAAUGUUGUAUAAAGUAUAAGUAAAGUUACAUAUGGGGCAGGCAGGGACUAGAAUAGAGUAGACAGGGACAGCAAUUUGUAUUCUUUGGAUGUAUCUUUUUUUUUUAUUUUAACUUUAUACUCACUUAAAUGUUUAAUUAUAUAACAAAGUUAAAAAUGCAAUGACUAAAAAUCAAAAUAAAUCUUAUAAAGUGGAUUUCCCAUUGGUUAUAUAAUCACACAGAGUAAACCAUUCCAAGUGACUUACAUAUACAGUAAUUUGUAGAAUAUUCCAAGUUGGGUAUAUCCUAAAGAUAAAAAGAAUUGUAAAAAAAAAAAAAAAUUAAAAAUAUUUUCAUGGAUCAUAUUGGUGAUGAUAGUGUUAAUAUUUUUAUUCUCAGGUUGUGUGAAUAUUUUGUGAUAAACUAUUAUGUAGGCUGCAUUGAGAAUAGAGGGUUUUCAUAUGUGAGAAAGGAGAAAUGAUAUAAGAUAAUGAGAUUGAGUAAAAACCCUAUAAACCUGAAUUUGAAUUGGAAGCAACAGUAUAAACUAAUGAUAAUGUACAUUUAUGUAUCUAUGUACAUGUUUAUGUAGAUAUGUGUGUAUAUAAUGUCUUAGAUCUUUGUACUGAAAAGGCAUUAAGCAUCCCUAUUACUGAGAUUGUGGUUUCUGAAUACCAUUUCCCACUAAAGGGAAUUAGGGCUUCUUUAAGGAAAUGACCAGUGCCAAGUCAAAGGCAAGAAAAAUACAAGAUAUGCCUGGAAUAAGUUGUAAUACCAGAAAGGUAAGGUAACCUCUGCUCUCGGAGGCAGAGGUUAGGAUUAUGUCAUAAGGUCUCAGGAACCAAUUUGAAUAAGGCUCUACUGUCCAAAGAUGGGACAGUUUGAACUUCAAUAAGAAUAACUACAAAGGAUUAAAACCUGUCACAUAGAUGUAAGUCUAUUAAUUCAUAACUUUUUAAAACUCACUGAUUGUCUUUAAGGAUGCUAGGAAGCUAUUACUAAUUGUUUUGAAAAUUAGUAAAUAAAAGUAAAAAAUUACUCAUUUAUUCUGUCCUUUCUAUACAGACUGCAUCAGGACAACUGAAUAGUUGAUGAGUUUUUUUUAUAGAAUUUUUCCAGCUAGUGAAUAAAGAAAGAAUGAUAGACUAUCAUGUGAUCGUUUUUCAACCCCGUUAAUGGAUUGCUUUAGUUGGUGAUCAUUGAUAACUGUUAAUAUCAAAAAAAGGGAAUUCAAUAGACUUUUGAACUUAACUGUUGGAAGUACAUACUACCUGCCACCUGUGAAGCAGUCUUGGCAAAAAAAAAAAAAAAAAAAAGUUUUUUGGUUUUUUUGUUUGUUUGUUUUUGGAAACAGAGUCACUGUUGCCCAGGCUAGAGUGCAAUGGUACUAUCUCAGCUCACUGCAACCUCCACCUCCCAGGUUCAAGCAAUUCUUGUGCCUCAGCCCCCGAGUACCUGGGACUACAGGUGCGUGCCACCACACCCGGCCAAUUUUUAUUAUUUUAGUAGAGAUGGGGUUUCACCACGUUACCCACGCUGGUCUCUAUCAAUUUACUGUAAAUACAAGAGUCAGAAGCACAUUAUUAAACUACAUCAUGGUAAUACAUUUGGCAAAAUCCAAACUAUAGGAAACAACCAGGUAACCUGAUUUCUUCAACAAAAAAAAAUUGUAAAGGGGGAGGAACCCAUAUGCAGAGAUUGAAGAGACAUAGUCAUCCAGUCACAGUGUGUAGACCUUAUUUGGAUCCUAAUUCAAACAAAGAAAAAACAAUUUGAGAAAUGUUAACACUGCCCAGGAGUUUCAUAUUAAGGAAUUAUUGUUUAUUUUAGAUAUGAUAGUCUGUAGUUGCUUUACAUCCUUUUAGAGGUAAAUAUGGAAAUAUUUACAGGUUGAAAUAAUAUGCUAUCUGAGAUUUGCUUGAGAAUAUUCUACUGGGAUUGGGUAGAUAGUGGACUGGGAUAUAGUUGAUACUUAAACCUGUAAUUGCAGCACUUUGGGAAGCUGAGGCAGGAGGAUCACUUGAGUCCAGGAGUUUGAGGUUGCAGUGAGCUAUGUUUGUGCCACGGCACCCCAGCCUCUGCAACAGAGCAAGACCCCAUUUCUAAAGGGGGAAAAAAAAACACCUGCCAAUUGGUAAAUGUUGGUUGAAACUUGGCAAUGGGUAGAGAUCCAUUAACUAUUUUCUCCACUUUUUUAUUGUAUAUUUUUUCAUUUUUAUUACAAAAAUUACAAAAGUAUCUCCUGCAAAGGAAGGAAAAACAAGUAAUAGGAAGGGAUGAGAUUAGAGAAGCUUAGUCAUUUAAUUGUCCUCUGUGUUUGAAUGCUAGGAGAUUUGAUAUUUAUGGAGUAUUAAUCACAAUCAAGAAACAUUUUACUGUUCAACAAUACACAGCACUAGAGAGAUUAAGAUCUGUCCCUUUACCUCAGUUGGGUGAUAAAGUAGAAACUGGAGACUUAAGGGUUGAGUAAUAGAAACAGCAGCACAGUGGACACAGAAGCAUGAGGUAGACGUGGCAGCUUCCUUCAGAAAGGUUGGUAUAGCACUGAAGACUUUUGAGACGCUUUCUUGUUUAGCAGGGGUGUGGAGGUUGGGGGGAUAAGACACACACUAGAUGAGGGAUUGAAGGCCUGGUCUUUGGUCUUGGCUUUGCCAUUUUACUCUUUUUUUUUUUUUUUUCUUGGAGACAGAGGAGUUUUGCCCUUGUCGCCUAGGCCACACACCUUGGCCUCCCAAAGUGCUGGAAUUACAGGCGUGAGCUACUGCACCUGGCCCAUUUUACUCUUUAUUUGACUUUGGAUAAGUCACUUUAAAGUCUCUACUUUGAUUUCCUCAUUUGGAGAAUAGAGAAUAUGCCUGUGCUGUCUACAUGGAAGAGUUAUUGUGAGAAUAAAAUGACUUAACACAUGAAAAAGCCCUUGGUAAACUGUAUUCCCAUUCUGAUGUAAGAUACUCCCACUCCAGUCAUUAAAAGGAACAUGAAGUUGGGGGGAAUGUUUAAAAAAGGGAGUGGAGAGGGAAGGUAUGUCAUUGCUUUUCUGUUUUAAUGUUUUUUUGUGAGGUUUUUUCCAUUUUUUAAGUUGUCACUUAAAAAUACAUAACAUUUACCAUUUUAACCAGUUUUAAGUGUAUAUAUAGUUCUGCAACAUUAAGUACAUUCACAUUGUUGUGCAGCCAUCACCACCAUCUCCAGAACUUUCUCAUUUUCCACAACUGAAACUUUGUGCUUACUGAACACUAACUUCCCAGCCCCUGACAACCAUCAUUCUACUUUCUGUCUCUAUGAAUUUGAUUACUCUAAGUACUUCAUAUAAGUGGAAUCCAUAUUCGUCCUUUUGUGACUGGCUUAUUUCACUUAACAUAAUGUUCUUAGGGUUCAUCUGUGUUUCAGCAUGUGUCAGAAUUUCCUUCCUUUUUAAGGCUGAAUAAUCUACUCUAUGUAUACACCACAUUUUGUUUUCCCAUUCAUCUAUCUGUGGACACCUGAGUUGCUUCUACCUUUUGGCUGUUGUGAAUAAUUUUGCUAUGAACGUGGGUGUACACAUCUGUUUGAGUCCCUGUUUUCACUUUUUUUGGUAUAUAUCCACAAAUGGAAUUGCUGGAUCAUAUAAUUCUAUGUUUAAUUAUUGAGGAAGCAGUGUGUUUUUAAAAAUUAUUUACUUUAUUGCUUAUGGAAACAUUUCCACAAGUCGUAUUUGAGGGUAUAUGUACGCUGUGAUCCAUGAGGCUUUUUGCUGGGAAAUCUUUUGUCUCCAAGUACUAAUCCAAUUUUCUUUUCUUUUCUUUUUUUUUUUUUUUUUGGAGACCGAGUCUGGCUCUGUCGCCUAGGCUGGAGUGCAGUGGUGCGAUCUCAGCUCACUGCAAGCUCCGCCUCCCAGGCUCACGCCAUUCUCCUGCCUCAGCCUCCCGAGGAGCUGGGACUGCAGGCGCCCACCACCACACCCGGCUAAUAUAUUUAGUAGAGACGGGGUUUCACUGUGUUAGCCAGGAUGGUCUCGAUCUCCUGACCUCAUGAUCCGCCCACCUCGGCCUCCCAAAGUGCUGGGAUUACAGGAUUGAGCCACCGUGCCCGGCCGCAAUUUUUUAAUCACACUCUUCUAAGAGGCUUAGACUGUGAAGGAAUAUGGAUCCCAAGAAAUAGUUUUUGGACUCAAAAUCUUGAAGAAUGAUUACAGAUAAGCCUUUCCUUACUAAAUGUUUAUUUUUUAAAACUAAUUUCAUUCAGCAGUUUUCAACUUAAUGCCUCCUAAGUGCCAGGUACUGUAUUAUGUGGUGAGGAUUUAGUGUUGAAUAAAUGAAAUUCAAGUGCUGAAAAGUACUACUGUAAAGAAAAUAAACUGAAGAAAGAGGAUAGUGAAUGAUGGGGUGGAAUGUUAUUUUAUAUAGGCUAACUAGGGAAGUCUUCUCCAAGAGGUAGUAUUUGAGCAAAGACUUCAGUAAAAAUGAGAGUAUGAAACAUGUGAAGAUGUUUCAGAAGAGUGGUACAGGCAAAGGGAAGAGCCCUGAGGUAGGAGUAAGAAAUGCUUUUCAAGUAGACAACUCAGGGAUCAGAUGACAGCCUAUCUUGACCAGUACCUAGUACCUAUAUGAGGAAAUCAAUUGUUGUAAGAUAGCUCUAGAAAGUAAAGUCACGUCUGGGUGUGCUGGCUCGUGCCUGUAAUCUGAGCACUUUGGGAGGCCAGGGCAGGAGGAUCAUUUGAGACCAGGAGUUCAAGACCAGCCUGGACAACAUUAGUGAGGCCCUGUCUCUACAGAAAAAAAAUGUUUUUAAUUAGCUGGACAUGGUGGCACACGCCUGCUCUAGCUACUUGGGAGGCUGAGGCUUGGAGGAUUGCUUGAGCCCAGGCACUGUGAGCUAUGAUUGUGCCACUGCACUUCAGCCUGAGCAACACAGUGAGACUCUGCCUCUUAAAAAUAAAAAAGAAAAGUACAGGAAAACUAAAAAUAGAAAAUUGUUAGGGAUAAUUUAUUUGCAUAUUCUGUUAAUCUAGAAAAUACUGUAUUUGUGGUGUGGGAGAUGUCAGGAAGAUAUUACUGCUGACAUGACAUUCCAAUAAUGAUUACUACAUAGAAGACAUAACCUUUUCCUCUGAAAUGUUAUUUUCUUGGCAGAGGGGCAUGUACAGUGAACCCAAAGGAUAUAUUUUAUCAUCUGUUCAGGGAAGACAGAAUGAGACAACUGAUAAAGAGAAUCUGAGUUUUAAGAAAUGAUCUCUAAAAAUCUUAGAUAAUAAAAUACUUUAAUAACCAAGUAUCUUACUGAUAUAUAUGACAGUGAUACAUAUAUUAUUAGGAGAACACUCAGACUCAGAUCUCAAGAGAGGUUAGAGAUCACCCAUAUUUUGCUGGGUGCUGUGCAGUAAUGUGAAGUUAUGCCAGAAAUAACUUUGCGCCUCAAGAAAUAAGCACCAUUACUUCUUAAGACUCUCCAUUUAUCUUUUUAGAAACAUUGAUAAGAUAUUUGUAAAUAAUAUCCUCAUUUAAAAGUAAAUGAAUUAUCUUGGGAGAAUGCUGUAUUGUAAUACAAGGAAUUUUACCUUUAGAAAUUAGAUAUUAUUAAUAGUAUUAGAAAACUUUUGUUUUUAGACUUCUUUAUGUUCUGUUUGAAUUGUUUCUUCCUUGAUAACGUCUUUUUUUUUUUUUUUUUAAAGAGAGAUGAGGUUGUUUUGUUGCCCAGGCUAGUCUGGAACUCCUGGCCUCAAGCAAUCCUCCUUAGCCUCCCAAAGUGCUGGGAUUAUAGGCGUGAGCCACCGUGCCUGGCCUCUUUAAUAUGUCUUUCCCAGAUUUCAAACCCAUUACCUUUAUCACCCUCAGUGGACCCAUAAAUUGCUUCUCCUAUAUGCUUCUUGGUUUACAGCAUUGUAACCACCCAGUUAUGCAAGGUAGAAACCUCAGUCAUCGUUUCCUUCUUCCUCUCCACCAUUCCCCUUACCAGUUUGGUGAGCAUUCUUCACUAUGUCUUCUAUGAUAAGGACCUCAUAUGUAUUACUUAAUUUUUUAUUAUAGAUGUCUACUAUGAUUUGCUGUUCCCCACAUUGCAUGUGUUGGGAACUUAAUCCCCAAAUCUGUAUGUCAGUUGAACGUAGGGCCUUUGGAAAGUAAUUAGGAUUAGAUAAAAUCAUCAGGGUGGGGCCACCAUAAUGGGGCUGGUGGCUUUAUAAGAGGAAGAGAGACCUGAGCUGACACGCAUGUUCUUGCCCUCUUGCUAUGUGGUGCCCUCAGCCAUGUUAGGGCACAGCAAGAAGGCCCUCACCAGAUAUUGGGGUGGUCUUGGACCUCCCACCCUCCAGAACUGUAAGAAAUAGAUUUUUUUAUAUAUUACCCAGUCUAUGAUAUUCUGUUACGGCAACAGAAAACAGACUAAGACAAGCUUCUAAACAAAUGGAAAAUAGAGUUUUAAGAUGCAGACUUUCAUUGCCUUAACAGGGCCAAGAAUAUCUAUUUCAUUCUGACAUACUUAAACUGUAAUAUCCUCUCCCAGUGUUUCUGCUACAAGUGGGUAGCACAGAACAAGCAAUGGGAUUAAGGAAAAAUUACCAUAGUUAUAAGAAAGCCCUCUAAUAAUGCUUGUGAGAGUGAGAGUUUUGUCUGGUUUUCUACUUCUUGUUUUUCAUAAGAGACCUUGUUGAUGUCUCUUACAGAGAGGGUCUUUUAUAGCUAAACGUUCUCAAAACUUGUUCAUCAUCACAACCACUAGUGCUUCUUUUACAAGGACCACUAUAUACAAGACUCUAAGUGUAGACUUCAGAAGAAACUUAGGAGGAACACAUUUUUCACUUAACAUGCCAACAAAGAUUCUUUAAAUAGCAAAUAUUCUGAUGGGCAGGAGCUCAUCAGAAUGGAGUGACUAGCCAGUAUUAAGCCAUUAUAUAUGACUUGUAACUUUUUCACUGAAAAUUUAAAGUAAUGGGUCCCCCACCCUCAUAUUUAUUUAGACUCAGUCUCCGUAAUGUGAAGAAAAAUAGAAUUUUACUAUGUAAUUACCUCAACUGCUAAGCCAUUAUUGUCUUCUUAUUUAUAAGAAUUUGAAUAAUUCAUAGGGCUAGUCACAUGCCUAUUCCUUUAAUGAUCUAACAGUUUGGAAUUUGAACUGUCUUCAUGAAGACUGCCCUGGAUGAGGAAACCUUUGAGUUUCUGUUUUGUUCUGUGUUCUCUUCUGUCUGUGCAGCCAUAGUCUCAGGCUUACUCUAGGGUUCACCCAGCAUGUUUGCUUAUCUCUCCAGCUCUACUAGUGGAACCCAUGGUAACUUAUCAAUAAGAAGUAUACCCUUGUAUUUUAAACAUUUGCUAAGUUGGUGUCAGAAAAUCUGAAUGUUUUGGCUUUGAAUGGAAUUUAGGAGAAAUUGCAUUUUUUCCCUUUAAAUUCAGUUGAUUUGAAUGUAUUCUCUGAUGUCAGUUCUAUUUCUCUCUGCAAGUCCUCUUUAAACUCAAAUCUAGGCCGGGCACGGUGGCUCACGCCUGUAAUCCCAACACUCUGGGAAGACGAGGCCGGCAGAUCACCUGAGAAAUGGAUGAAAAGAGGCUGCUGGAUCCAGGGUUGAAGGUUCAUAAAGGCCUCUGGGAUUAUACUCUGAAGAACCCGCAGACGGAAUGCCUGAGUGACUGAAGAAAAUGGGUGCUAAUGCAUCUAAUUAUCCUCAUUCAUGUUCCCCGAGGGUAGGGGGAAAUUCACAGGCCCAACAGACUUUUAUAGGGACCUCAUCCUAUUCUCAGCAAGGCUAUGGUUGCGAAUCAAAGUUGUAUAGCCUUGACCAUGGCCAUGAGAAACCACAAGACAAAAAAAAGAGAACCUCUGGUCUUGCCACCCUCAAAAAGAAGUUUAUUAAGCGUCGGAAAUCUAAUAGGUCUGCCGAUCAUGCCAAGCAGAUGCGAGAACUCCUCUCUGGGUGGGAUGUUAGAGAUGUCAAUGCAUUAGUGGAGGAAUAUGAGGGAACAUCAGCAUUAAAGGAGCUUUCUCUACAAGCCAGUUUGGCUAGACCAGAAGCCCGGACAUUGCAGAAAGAUAUGGCUGAUCUUUAUGAGUACAAGUAUUGUACUGAUGUAGACUUAAUAUUUCAAGAAACUUGUUUUCCUGUUCAUCGUGCCAUUUUGGCAGCAAGGUGUCCAUUUUUUAAAACACUGCUUUCUUCCUCACCAGAGUAUGGGGCAGAGAUAAUAAUGGACAUCAAUACAGCUGGUAUUGAUAUGCCCAUGUUUUCUGCUUUGUUACACUACCUUUAUACAGGAGAGUUUGGAAUGGAGGACUCAAGGUUUCAAAAUGUCGAUAUCCUUGUUCAGCUUAGUGAAGAAUUUGGAACACCAAAUUCCCUUGAUGUAGAUAUGCGUGGACUCUUUGAUUACAUGUGUUAUUAUGAUGUCGUCCUUAGUUUUUCUUCAGACUCUGAACUGGUUGAAGCUUUUGGUGGAAAUCAGAACUGUUUAGAUGAAGAGCUCAAAGCCCACAAGGCUGUUAUUUCUGCACGGUCCCCAUUUUUUCGAAAUUUAUUACAAAGGAGGAUACGAACUGGUGAAGAAAUCACAGACCGAACUUUGAGGACUCCCACAAGAAUUAUAUUAGAUGAGUCCAUUAUACCAAAAAAAUAUGCAACAGUGAUAUUACACUGUAUGUAUACCGACGUGGUGGACCUCUCUGUUUUGCACUGUAGCCCCUCUGUGGGGAGUCUCAGUGAAGUUCAGGCUCUCGUCGCAGGGAAGCCAAACAUGACCAGGGCAGAAGAAGCCAUGGAACUUUACCACAUAGCACUGUUCUUGGAAUUUAACAUGCUUGCACAAGGCUGUGAGGAUAUCAUUGCUGAGAGCAUCUCAUUAGAUACCUUAAUUGCCAUCCUCAAGUGGAGUUCUCAUCCAUAUGGCUCUAAAUGGGUGCACCGACAAGCUUUACAUUUCCUCUGUGAGGAAUUUUCCCAGGUCAUGACUUCGGAUGUUUUUUAUGAACUCAGCAAAGACCAUCUGCUUACUGCUAUCCAGUCUGACUACCUACAGGCAAGUGAACAAGAUAUCCUUAAAUAUCUGAUUAAAUGGGGAGAGCAUCAGUUGAUGAAAAGAAUAGCAGAUAGAGAGCCAAACUUACUGAGUGGCACUGCCCAUAGUGUGAACAAAAGAGGUGUAAAAAGACGGGACCUGGACAUGGAAGAGCUCAGAGAGAUCCUUUCUUCUCUCUUACCUUUUGUGCGAAUUGAACACAUCUUACCUAUAAACAGUGAAGUCUUAAGUGAUGCAAUGAAAAGAGGCUUGAUUAGUACUCCUCCAUCAGAUAUGCUUCCUACAACAGAAGGUGGGAAGUCAAAUGCCUGGUUACGGCAAAAAAAUGCUGGCAUCUAUGUUCGUCCUCGACUCUUCUCUCCCUAUGUGGAAGAAGCAAAGUCAGUGCUAGAUGAGAUGAUGGUGGAACAAACGGAUCUUGUGCGCUUGCGAAUGGUUAGAAUGUCCAAUGUGCCAGACACGCUCUACAUGGUCAAUAAUGCCGUGCCACAGUGUUGUCACAUGAUCAGCCACCAGCAGAUCAGCAGCAACCAGUCAAGCCCUCCUUCAGUUGUAGCCAACGAAAUUCCAGUUCCUCGUCUCCUCAUUAUGAAAGACAUGGUCAGACGACUGCAGGAACUGCGGCACACGGAGCAGGUGCAGAGGGCCUAUGCCCUGAACUGCGGGGAAGGCGCCACUGUCAGCUAUGAAAUUCAGAUUCGAGUGCUAAGAGAGUUUGGUCUUGCAGAUGCUGCUGCAGAGCUGUUGCAGAAUCCUCACAAAUUCUUUCCUGAUGAACGUUUUGGGGAUGAAAGUCCACUCUUGACAAUGAGACAGCCUGGGAGAUGUCGCGUAAACAGUACACCUCCUGCAGAAACCAUGUUUACAGAUCUGGACUCUUUUGUGGCCUUCCAUCCACCCUUGCCCCCUCCACCACCUCCCUACCACCCCCCAGCUACCCCAAUCCAUAACCAACUCAAAGCAGGCUGGAAGCAAAGACCUCCCAGUCAGCACCCUUCACGUUCAUUUUCUUAUCCCUGUAAUCAUUCGCUGUUCCACUCCAGAACAGCUCCUAAAGCUGGCCCUCCCCCAGUCUACUUGCCGAGUGUGAAAGCUGCACCGCCUGAUUGUACCAGCACUGCAGGACUGGGCAGACAGACGGUGGCUGCUGCUGCCGCCACCACCACCUCAACAGCAACAGCAGCAGCAGCAGCAGCAUCUGAGAAGCAAGUGCGAACACAACCUGUGCUGAAUGAUCUGAUGCCAGACAUCGCGGUGGGUGUGUCCACACUGUCACUCAAGGACAGGAGGCUUCCAGAGCUUGCUGUAGACACAGAAUUAAGCCAGUCAGUUUCUGAAGCAGGACCAGGGCCUCCCCAGCAUCUGUCGUGUAUUCCACAGAGACAUACACACACUUCUCGGAAAAAACACACACUAGAGCAAAAAACAGACACCAGAGAAAAUCCACAGGAAUAUCCGGAUUUCUAUGACUUCUCAAAUGCUGCUUGCAGACCUUCUACUCCUGCUCUCAGCAGACGCACCCCUUCCCCUUCGCAAGGUGGAUAUUUUGGUCCCGAUCUGUACAGCCACAAUAAGGCAUCACCAAGUGGCUUAAAGUCAGCCUACCUACCUGGUCAGACGUCUCCUAAAAAACAGGAAGAAGCUAGGAGAGAAUAUCCACUUUCCCCUGACGGGCAUCUACACAGACAAAAGAAUGAGCCGAUACACCUGGAUGUCGUUGAGCAACCUCCCCAGCGGUCAGACUUUCCUUUGGCAGCCCCAGAAAAUGCUAGUACCGGUCCAGCCCAUGUCAGGGGACGAACUGCAGUAGAAACUGACUUGACUUUUGGGCUGACUCCUAACAGACCUUCACUUUCUGCAUGUAGCUCUGAAGCUCCCGAAGAGAGAUCCGGUAGAAGACUGGCAGACAGUGAGUCCCUGGGCCAUGGAGCUCAGAGAAAUACAGAUUUGGAAAGGGAAGAUUCAAUAAGCAGAGGAAGGAGGUCACCAAGCAAGCCGGACUUCCUCUACAAAAAGUCUGCCCUCUGAGAGCAACCUCCAAGUCGUCUGUGCCUGAGAUGUGAAACAUCCCAUUUUAUGAUGUAACCCAACAACUUACAGACCAGUUCAUCAAUGCCAGCUGAUAACUCGGUUUCACAUGAUUUUGUUCUAGUUUUUGUGUAUAUAUGUGUUUAUUAGACAUGGCAUGCUAAGAAGGUUUUGUUUUUUUUUUUUAAUGUUGCAUCUGUCUAAUUUGUCUUUGAACAAUUAUGUCGGGAGGCAUUUUUAAGAACAAGCAGGCUGGCACUUUUUAUUUCUCUUUACAAAUGAUGGAAUUUUUUUGCACUUGUACAUUUAUUUUCUCUGUAUUGAUUUUAUAUCAGUAUGUUAAACUUUAUUGCCACAUUUAAAGGACUGUAUUUUCAUACUUUUUUGCAUUUUACCUUUCAUCUACCAAUCCAUGUGCAUUGGAUUGCACACUAAGAUGUAUUUUCUUACGAAAUAGUUCUGUGUUUAUUUUUUAAUUAUAGAAAUUCCAAAGAACAGCACAUCAGAAUGCUCCUCUCUUUUCAGUAAUUGUUUUAGUUCAGAGAUCUUCCCGCUCAGCCUCCAUAAAUCUAAUGUCAUUUUUUUUUUAAUAAGUCCUAGGAGCUGGGCUUCAUUCCUCCAGCGGGAGUCCAGUCAGGGUCCUGAAGUUUGCUGGUUCAGGAAAGAACAGGAAAGAGAAAAGCCUUCUGUGCCCAGGCUAAAGCUGUUACAUUUCCACAGUGUGGAUGCAGUCAGAAUCCCUGCACAUUCUGGUCAUAAGGAUUAGAGUCACCAGAUGAGGCUCUAAACAGAUCGCAUCCCUUGGAAUUAGAAAGCAGUGGAGACCGGGCGCAGUGACUCACACCUGUGAUCGGCACUUCGGAAGGCCGAGGCGGGCAGAUCACUGAAGCUCAGGAGUUCAAGACCAGCCUGGGCAACAUGGCGAAACUCCAUUUCUAUAAAAAAUACAAAAAAAAAAAAAUCUAGCCAGGCGUGGUGGUGCGUGCCUGUAGUCCCAGCUACUUGGGGGGCUGAGGUGGCAGGAUCGCUUGAGCCUGGGAGGUUGAGACUGCAGUGAGCCAAGAUUGCACCACUGUGCUCCCACCUGGGCAACAGUGAGACCCUGUCUCAAAAAAAAAAAAAAAGGCAGUGGAAAUAGAGAAGUAACUUAAAGGUCACACUGACAGAAUUUCUGGUUCUGAGCGUCAACUCUCCAGCUGUGAUGGCGGAACUGACUGCUUGCUGCCUUUAAUUGUCUUGCUCUCUAUGGGAAAAAAACAAAAGGGCUUCAGUCUCAUGGAUGUUAUUUGGUGUUUGUAAAGAUACGUUUUCUUUUAAACGAUUUUCAAAAUAUGUCUAAAUUUUGGUGUUGUGUAAUGCAUAAUGCUUUCUCACCAACAGAAAAAAGGAAAAAAAUUGUUUUCAGUUAAACACUACAUGUCCUACUUGAACUCCACUGGGACGCUGGUUUGGCAUUUACUAAACCACUGAGCACAUGGGGUCUUUCAGGAUCCUCUCCCUUGGAAGGGCAAUGUGUGAGCUAAGGACUGUUUUUUUUCUUACUCUCCAAUGUAAAUAUAUGAGUAUUUGAGUUUUUAAAUCACUUCAACAUUAUUUGAGCAUUUACUUUGUAUUUUUACAAACACAUAAACACACAGCCGUAGCACUUAGAAGAAAAGAGGCUUUCUAAGCAUUCCUUCCUCUGCAGGAUAUUUGGGAUCCUCUUUUCUAUGUAUGUAUAUAUAUAAAAAACUAUGAAUCACUCACACUCACUCGAAAACUAUGCAGGGCUAGGGAGCGUUUAUGAGCUACCGGGUAAAUGAAUUACAUGCACUUUGAAGUAAAUAGGUUUUCUAUUGGGUGUCAACAACGCUGAUUUCUCCCAAAACUAUAGUUUCUCUUACGGUCUUUUCCUCCUUUACCCUGUGGAUAUACACUCAGGAAUAAUCUGACAUUUUAGAAAAGCCGAACAGUAGAUAGUCUCCAAGAUGGGAAACAUGUCGUGUGUCUGCACGCCCCGGCAAACUGCCGCCACUCGUUCUGCUGCCUGACUGGUUAGCUGCUGUGCGGGUGCGCUCGGUGACACUGGUGGUGGUGCACGCUCCCGAGCUCCCAGAGUUAACACUAAUCUGCAGGUCGGCUGUGCAUCGCAUUCGAGGCUCCUUUUUUAAAGAGAAAAGCAUAGGCCUCUGUUCUCAUUUGUAAGAAGUUUGACUCAUAAUAGAAGACGGUGUCUUUUGAAGCCCAGUCUCUGUCUGUCUUCAGAAACAAAAGUGAAUGCCGUCAUGUUCCUUGAUGUGUGUUUCUGCCACAUAUGUAUGUUGACAUGUUCAUGUACUGCGCCGGUACUGCAAGUAAGACUCAACAGACCUAAUUUGGAUGGGGAGAAAAACUCUCAUCCCUGACCCUUCCCCCCCCGCAAAUGUUAGACCAGAGCUGUUGAUCCCACACAUUCAUUUUUCUGAAAAUUCAUGAACUAUUCUCUCAUAUCCCUGAAAUAUAAAAGUAAGUGGCCACUAUUCCUAAGAUUAUUUAGUUUAUAAAGUUUGCUUUUAAUCAUACAAUAGCUUACCUGGCUAAAACUUUGCGUAUAAAGGGAAAACUUGCUUUAAUCUGUGGGAUUGCGGACCGAUGCGACUUGCAGAAGGUAAACAGGCGUGGGUUUUGUGUGCGUUAGGUUAGGUGUUAGUGGACUUUUAAUGUAUCUUGUGAAGUAUGGUUACUAGGGUAGGUUCAAGAGCUACAUGCCUCUGGCUUUUGAACCCAUCUAUUAAAUCUUUUUUAAUGCUGUACUAAGAUAAAUGUGAAGUCUGAGUAAGGUUGCUCUCAGAAAAAAAAAAAAAGCAUAUAUAUAUAUAAAAUAAAAUUUAGGCCAUGGGAACUGGCAUUUUACUUGGUAUAGGAAUUUAAUGAGAACCAAAUCACAAAAAUACCAGAUCUCCUUUUGAGAUCGUGGACAAUCAGGCCUUUGGACAAUCACCGCUUCCAGUGCCCGCUGUGCGUUGAGGUUAGAGACCUACCGUUUACACGCUAGAGCCGAGAGGACGUUCAAGUUUCUUAAAGAUGCUGUUGGUCUUUUUUCUUAUGUUAUUGUUUUAGUUUUGUGAUUUUGAUGAAUAAUUGAAGUUCAGAGUCACCCGUGGCUCCUAAGGAAAAAACAGCAUCAUGAAAGGCAAAAAGUAUUUGAAACGUAAUUGUUUCAAUUUUCCACGCCCGUUCUCACAUGCCCCCUUUAGCUUUAUUUCUGGGAACAUGUCACUAGACCUCAGCUAGCCUGACACCGCAAUAACCCGUUAGGCUUUGAGGCUUUUCAGUGAAUUCUUGACAUUUAAAUCUUCUUAUAGAAUUCUUUAUGAAGCCUUAACUAAUUCUUGUUUUUGCUUCCUCAGAAACUUUUUAUUGCAUCUGCCAUCCUUCAUUGGAUUUUUGUUUUGGUUUGUUGUUGCCAUUCUAGCAAUGAGCUUAGUCCUUGUACAUCUGCAUUAAGGUGCCGAUGCAGAAGGCAAAUUGGAAACACGCGCCAGCGGCAGUGGGGCUCAAAGCCGACCUCCAUGCAUCAUUCUCUAGAGUUGAAAGGAUUGACAUUUCUCAGUAACUACCCGGCAAAAUAUAUAUUUUCAUAAUGUUGAAUUUGCCUUUUAGGAAAACAAUGUUUCAUGAAACACUUGUAAGAUACUUAUUUUGAAAUUAAUUAUAAGGCAUUCAUAUUUUUAGGACUGAAUUCAAAGGGAAAUGCUUCUUUGACUUUUUUUCAUUGUUCGGUUGACUUUCAGCUUUCUGGAGUGACAAAGCAGCAGUGAUGGGUGCUAUUCCUGGUUCUGUGGUGGUUUACUUUGUCUACUAAGUGAUUUACUUUCAAACCUCAUUACAGAUAAUCUUACUAAAAGACUUAACAUGCACACUGCUAAAAGGUGUUUUACUGUUUUCCAUUAACGCUGUUGUAUGAACAAUAUUUGGUGACAUGUUGUCUUUUUGUCCUGUAGAUUGUCAUAUCUGUUAUGUAGUUAUCCUUUUGGCAAGUCCUUUGAUUUUUUUUUCCUCUAGAAAAUCCUCAGACUGUCAAUCUUCCAUAUUUUGAAUAUUAUAAUGCUGUGGCCAUUUCUAUAGAAAGAUUACUUGCAAGUGUGUGUCUUGAAAAUAACCUCUUGUAUUUGUGUGUUUAUGUGAGUUCUGUCUAAGAGAUCAGAUAAGCUCUGGAAGCUUCAUCAUCUGUACCUACAUGUAACUGUAUCUGGGUUACAUGGGCAGGCGGUACCAAGUCCUGCUCUUCGAUGGGGUGGCUGAGAGAUAAAGGUUCCUGAACUCUCCUUGCUGUGUAUGCACCACAUCUGUACUUCAGAGAGGUGGAAAAUCAUCUACAACACUGCGUUUCUUGUGGUUGUGCUGUUACUGGUAUAAAGUCAAGUGCCUUCAAUGCUAAAGGCUCAGAAAUUUUUCUUAAACUGAUUUCAUGUCCUAUGCAAGUGUUUUCUACAACCUGCAUAACCAGUACUUUGUAAAACUUGUUUACGCUUCAAUUGUACAUAGUGAUUUUUAAAGAAAUAUAUAGUAUUUUUAUUUAGGUACCUCCAAACUUGAAUUCGUCUGUGUGAAGCAUUGUAAAACGAUACAUUUCUCUUUUGAGUACCAUUACAGUUGUACAGAGGUUUUCACUGCUUCUAUUUUUCUACUGUUACUGAUAAGCAUGUAACACUGACUUUAUCCUACAUAUAGUUGGCAUUUCAAAUAAAUGGCUUGUAUAGAA